GGAAGUGCAUGAGCUGCCGAUGUGGUGCUUAGUGAUUGCGGUUUCGGUCGCUCUCCCGUGUUUCCCGGGCUGGGUAUUUGCCUCGCACCAUGGCGGUUUCUGCACUACGGGGACCUGGCUGAGUUGCGGAUGGAGCUCUAUAGCUCACCAGGCUGGUGGGGAGAAUGAGGAGGACCGUGGCCUCCUGACGGCAUCUCAUCAUUCCUCUGCAGCCCAAGGGCAAAGUGGGCACGAGAGGGAAGAAGCAGAUAUUUGAAGAGAACAGAGAGACUCUGAAGUUCUACCUGCGGAUCAUACUGGGGGCCAAUGCCAUUUACUGCCUUGUGACGUUGGUCUUCUUUUACUCAUCUGCCUCAUUUUGGGCCUGGUUGGCCCUGGGCUUUAGUCUGGCAGUGUAUGGGGCCAGCUACCACUCUAUGAGCUCGAUGGCACGAGCAGCGUUCUCUGAGGAUGGGGCCCUGAUGGAUGGUGGCAUGGACCUCAACAUGGAGCAGGGCAUGGCAGAGCACCUUAAGGAUGUGAUCCUACUGACAGCCAUCGUGCAGGUGCUCAGCUGCUUCUCUCUCUAUGUCUGGUCCUUCUGGCUUCUGGCUCCAGGCCGGGCCCUUUACCUCCUGUGGGUGAAUGUGCUGGGCCCCUGGUUCACUGCAGACAGUGGCACCCCAGCACCAGAGCACAAUGAGAAACGGCAGCGCCGACAGGAGCGGCGGCAGAUGAAGCGGUUAUAGCCAUUGACAUUGUGGCCACAGGCCACUGGCCCUGGGUGGCUCUGUCAGGGUGCACAGCCCCUCAUGCCUGGAGCAAUGAGGGUCUAGUCCAGGGGCCAAAAGCAGUCUGAGGUAUUGGGUAUACUUAUACUCUAUAGGGUCGUUGAAUAAAUGGCUUAGAAUGUG